UUCUGCUAACGGGAGCCAAACAAAAAGAUGGACAUCUUUCAAGAUCAAUGUCUGUAAAACAAGCUUCCAAUUCUAAUGAGAAUGUUAACACUCAGGCCCCGUGUCCCGGGGGUAUUGUAAACAGAGUCUACUCCAGGUGCUGGUUGUAACGUUGUUUUCCCUAGACCUCUGGCUCAUGUUUCCAGAACGUUGGUCCCUGACUGGUAGGCUGCACCCUCUCCCUAGGGUACAGAUUGGGCACCGCAGGGAUGGGUCAGAGCUCUGGCUUGGACAGUCCCAUGAGCCACCGCAAGAGCACCUUAAAUCAGAGGAGCGACUCUUCUGGUUUUGCCCUAGAUAGUGUCAUUCAUUGCAGAUGUUGGGGCAAUACCACUGAGCAGGAGAUGCCUGAGAGUGAAGUGGGGGCUCCCUGGGUCAGGAAAGCUGCCCUUCUCCCACCACGUCCUCAGCUCUCCUGGAAGGUCUGCUAUUCAGCCUUGGGUUCUCAUUUUUCUUUUUCCCAGCUAACCCUUGAAGACUUUUUGUUUUUUUUGUAGCAUUUUCUUUGUUGAAGGAUUAUUCUGAUCUCAAAUAGGCAAUAUGUUCUCUUUUAAAAUAUAAAUUCUUAUUCAGUAAGUAUUGGGGGUGUUAGCAGAUUUCCUUUUGAAUUGCUGGGUUUUCAUUUUGGGUUGUUGUUUCUGUUUUUGAGACAGGGUCUUGCCCUAUUGCCCAGGCUGGAAUGCAGUGGCACAAUCUUGGCUCACUGCAGCCUCCAUCUCCCAGGCUCAAACAAUCCUCCCACCUCAACCUCCUGAGUAGCUGGGACUACAGGUGGGCACCACCACGCCCAGCUAAUUUUUCUGUAUUUUUUUAUAUUGCCAGAGUGUAUUCGUCUAUUCUCACAUUACUCUAAAGAACUACCGGAGAUUGGGUAAUUUAUAAAGAAAAUAGGUUUCACUGGGUCAAGGUUCUGCAGGCUGUACAGGAAGCACGGCAGCAUCUGCUUCUGGGGAGGGCUCAGGGAGCUUUGAUUCAUGGCGGAAGGCAAAGCGGGAGCAGGCGUCUUACGUGGCAGGAGCAGGACCAAGAGACGGGUGGGGGGUACUACCCACUAUUAAACAACCAGGUCUCGUGAGAACUCACUCACUCUAUGGUGGGGGAUGGUACUAAACCAUUCAUAAGAACUCUGCCACCUUCCUCCAACACUGAAGAUUACAAUUCGACAUGAGAUUUGGGGAGGGACACUGAUCUGAAUCAUAUUACAGUGUUUCCCCAUGUUGCCCAGUCUGGUCUCAAACUCCUGGGCUCAAGGAUCCUCCUUGGCCUCGCAGAGUGCUGGAAUUACAGGCAUGAGCCACCACGCUUGGCCAAAUUACUGUGAAGGCAGGCACUGUGCUGGUGUGUUCACCAUUAUACGACCUGGUAGAAAAGGCAGUGCUUGGUAGAUACGUGCUCAUAAAUAUCUGUUUCCUGACUGACUGUUAAAUAAGUAAAUAAACAAAGAGAUUCUUUAUGUGACCAUGCAGAUUUAUCUAUUCAAUUAAGUAUUCCCAGAGCGGUUGCUGCAUUCAUUGAGGACAAUGUUUUCUUCUGUCUUUGUCUAAACUCUUAAGUACUAAUUAAUUUUUUUUAACAAAUGAGACAAAUAAAUGCUUUUUAAAUUUAUGAGAAGGAAGGGAUUGUUUCUUUGAAUUGAUCAACUCUUUCAAAUGAAAAUCCACUUAAGUCCACCUAAAGCAGUGCGGUGAAAAAUAGCUGGAGAAAGAGAAGUGGGACCUUUUAAGUAGGGAGUAGCAGGAGUAAGAAAGAAAAGAAACCUGCAUUCUUGGCAAGGGAGGGAAAGGCAGUUUGAGAGUUUUCUGAUUGAAGGCUUUUAGAUGAAAUUCUUGACUCAGGUGUUUUCACUGAAAUCUGUUGGUAGCAGAUUAAGUUUCGCUGCUAAACUUUUUAUCCUUGCAUAUAGUAGUAAUCCGUAUACAAGGUUAAAUGUCUGUUUUUGGCACCUGAUGAUCUUUUUAAGAUUGUUUAGGCAAAUGAUCUGUAAAGACCGGAACCCUCAAAUAGCGUCUAUUGUAUUUGCUUGUAUGAUUUCUCUCUUUCUGUCUGGUAUAUUCAUUAGCAAAUGGGACAAGGAAGGCCUAUUUGAGUGUCCGAGUCUGUUAACCUUUAGGUGCCAGCCUCCCCUUAAUAUAAUACUCAUUAACUGUGAGGUUCUCCUCCCCCACCUUCUAAAGAACACUGAUGCACCAGGAACUGUCAGCAAUUCAUGGCAAAGCCACGAACCAAGAUCUAACAGUUCUCGGAACCAAGAUCUAACGUCGGAACCAAGAUGAGCAUCGGUUCAUUGGAACCAAUAUCUAAGAGUUCUCCCUUCCUUUACAUUUCUUCUCCGACAAGAAUGAUUUGAAACAGAGGCUGCUGGUUUGCCUAGAAGAGUCCAUUUAUAUUCACAACAUUAAAGACAUGAAGCUGUUGAAGACCCUCCUGGAUAUUCCUGCAAACCCAACAGGUCUAUGUGCUCUCUCUAUCAACCAUUCCAAUUCUUACCUGGCCUAUCCUGGAAGCCUGACUUCAGGGGAGAUUGUGCUUUAUGAUGGAAACUCCCUGAAAACAGUCUGCACUAUUGCUGCCCAUGAGGGAACACUAGCUGCCAUCACCUUCAAUGCCUCAGGCUCCAAACUAGCAAGUGCGUCUGAAAAAGGCACAGUCAUCCGGGUGUUCUCUGUCCCUGAUGGGCAAAAGCUCUAUGAGUUCCGGAGAGGGAUGAAAAGGUAUGUGACAAUCAGCUCUCUAGUGUUCAGUAUGGAUUCACAAUUCCUCUGCGCCUCCAGUAACACCGAGACGGUACACAUCUUCAAGCUGGAACAGGUCACCAACAGUCGACCAGAAGAGCCUUCGACCUGGAGUGGCUACAUGGGAAAGAUGUUUAUGGCUGCUACCAACUACCUCCCUACCCAGGUGUCAGACAUGAUGCAUCAGGACAGGGCUUUUGCCACUGCACGCUUGAACUUCUCCGGACAGAGGAACAUCUGUACCCUCUCAACGAUCCAGAAGUUGCCACGGCUGCUAGUUGCGUCAUCCAGUGGACACCUUUAUAUGUACAAUUUGGAUCCUCAGGAUGGAGGAGAGUGUGUCUUAAUCAAAACCCACAGCUUGCUUGGCUCAGGAACAACAGAAGAGAAUAAAGAAAAUGACCUCAGACCUUCCUUACCUCAGUCUUAUGCAGCGACCGUAGCCAGACCAAGUGCAUCUUCAGCCUCCACGGUGCCAGGUUAUUCUGAGGACGGCGGGGCGCUGCGAGGAGAAGUUAUUCCUGAACAUGAGUUUGCGACGGGACCAGUGUGUCUUGAUGAUGAGAAUGAGUUUCCUCCUAUAAUCUUGUGCCGUGGAAAUCAGAAGGGCAAAACGAAGCAGUCAUGAUGAGAAGCACACCUCAGAAAUCAGGACAUCCCCCCUAUCAGGUGGUUUUGGAGAAAACAAGGAAGGCGGAAGAAUGGAGUGCAAUUGUGUGAGCAGAAAGGGGGGCAGGAAUCCCGGGUGCUCCACUGCUUAAACCACAGGACCUGGUUAACUCCUCACCAAGCUUCCCACGACCCUGGUUGCCAAUGGGCGCGGGAGACAUUGUAUACACAUCAUGCUAUUUAAAAUACGUUCAAACUAUAGUGUAAAUGCUAAUUAACCAUAUUGGUAUAUAACCGGAAUUUUAUAUUAAAAGGGGCCUCCUUUUUAAAUAUAUGCCGUGUAAAAAAUGUACUUAUAGGAACAUCUCUUUGAAUUGUAUUUCUUGUAUAUUACAUACUUAGAGAGAGACUCUUUUAGCCAGGCAAAGUCUUUUUUGGCUGUGGCUGGAAUAAAUCAUUUAUUACUUGGGAGUCCCAUUUUGGACACUAAUAAUAAAAUCAUGGCAAUGCA